AACCAAUUGCACCACGACCGGAUGGAAGAGCCCAGCUGACACAACCAAGACGAGUCUCAGUGUCUAGGGAAGCUUGGGGUUCUGCUCCUUUUACUUCAGGCGAACCUGAACUCAGUUAAUGCAAUUUUGAAGCAUGCCCUGAAUAGAUUCAGUCAUUAUCAAGUCAAACUAAAAACGGUGAAAGGUUGCGACUAUUACCAAAUAGGAAAAAUCUGAAGACAUAAGAACUACACAUGAGGAAUAUGUCAUUUAGCACUUUCACUUUUUGAUCUCCACAGAAGACAAUGAGAAGUCAUACCAUAACAAUGACGACAACUUCAGUCAGCAGCUGGCCUUACUCCUCCCACAGAAUGCGCUUUAUAACCAAUCAUAGCGACCAACCGCCACAAAACUUCUCAGCAACACCAAAUGUUACUACCUGUCCCAUGGAUGAAAAAUUGCUAUCUACUGUGUUAACCACAUCCUACUCUGUUAUUUUCAUCGUGGGACUGGUUGGGAACAUAAUCGCCCUCUAUGUAUUUCUGGGUAUUCACCGUAAAAGAAAUUCCAUUCAAAUUUAUCUACUUAACGUAGCCAUUGCAGACCUCCUACUCAUCUUCUGCCUCCCUUUCCGAAUAAUGUAUCAUAUUAACCAAAACAAGUGGACACUAGGUGUGAUUCUGUGCAAGGUUGUGGGAACACUGUUUUAUAUGAACAUGUACAUUAGCAUUAUUUUGCUUGGAUUCAUCAGUUUGGAUCGCUAUAUAAAAAUUAAUCGGUCUAUACAGCAACGGAAGGCAAUAACAACCAAACAAAGUAUUUAUGUCUGUUGUAUAGUAUGGAUGCUUGCUCUUGGUGGAUUCCUAACUAUGAUUAUUUUAACACUUAAGAAAGGAGGGCAUAAUUCCACAAUGUGUUUCCAUUACAGAGAUAAGCAUAACGCAAAAGGAGAAGCCAUUUUUAACUUCAUUCUUGUGGUAAUGUUCUGGCUAAUUUUCUUACUAAUAAUCCUUUCAUAUAUUAAGAUUGGGAAGAAUCUAUUGAGGAUUUCUAAAAGGAGGUCAAAAUUUCCUAAUUCUGGUAAAUAUGCCACUACAGCUCGUAACUCCUUUAUUGUACUUAUCAUUUUUACUAUAUGUUUUGUUCCCUAUCAUGCCUUUCGAUUCAUCUACAUUUCUUCACAGCUAAAUGUAUCAUCUUGCUACUGGAAAGAAAUUGUUCACAAAACCAAUGAGAUCAUGCUGGUUCUCUCAUCUUUCAAUAGUUGCUUAGAUCCAGUCAUGUAUUUCCUGAUGUCCAGUAACAUUCGCAAAAUAAUGUGCCAACUUCUUUUUAGACGAUUUCAAGGUGAACCAAGUAGGAGUGAAAGCACUUCAGAAUUUAAACCAGGAUACUCCCUGCAUGAUACAUCUGUGGCAGUGAAAAUACAGUCUAGUUCUAAAAGUACUUGAGGUAAACAUACUAAAAUGAAUUAUAUAAUGCAGCCUCUUAAUUCUUUGAAGAACUAAAAAAUUAGGAAACAAAGUUCUAGCAUUUACAAAACUCAGAUCUCAAAGCUCUGCUUGUAUUUGUGAUAUUUCAUUUGCUUAACUGUAAACCAUUUCAAGGUACUAACUUUUAAAUCUGUAUGUAAAAUCUUUUCAAAAUACAUUUUUAAGCUAAUACUCUUAACAUAGAUUAUGAAGUUAAGUGAAAUUUAUGGCUCUAACAGCAAAAUAAUUAAAGUGCCAUAGUUUCUCAAGUGACUAAAGUAGUUAUUAAAAUCAAGCACUUGAUACUAAUUUGAAGUGUGUUUAAAAGUAAAUGAUUUGGGAACUGACAAUGUGUCAGAAAAUAUAUGUUCAUUUAUCAUUUUAAAAUCUUGUAUAAUUUGCCACUGUAUUCAUUUAUGCCUAAAUCUCUAUAACAGAUGAAAAGAUAAUUAAUAAAAUCCUAAUUAAAAAAUGA